GAGAAAGGGUUCAGAGUCAGGCACAGGCAGGCAGACAGGACCCCAAGCAGGACUGGCCUUCCAGACAGGAAAGAGGGUUGCGGAGACACAGGAGGCCAGUUGAGAGUGGCAGAGGAGAAAGGAGUUUCAUGGGAGGAUGGGGCUUGGAGAGAGAUGAGGGAGGGAAAACGGGGGCCGCCAUGCAUCCUCAGCUUCCGGGGGACUUUGGAGAGGGUCGAGGCUCAGUGGGAGCUGGAGGCCCAGGGCCCCGGCCAGUGCCCAGCCCCGCUGGGAGACCCGGCCAGCACCACGGACGGCGCCCAGGAAGCCCGAGUCCCCCUGGACGGGGCCUUCUGGAUUCCGAGGCCCCCGGCAGGUUCGCCCAAGGGCUGCUUCGCUUGCGUGUCCAAGCCCCCUGCCCUGCAGGCUCCGGCGGCCCCUGCCCCUGAGCCCUCGGCCUCUCCCCCGAUGGCGCCCACACUGUUCCCCAUGGAGUCCAAGAGCAGCAAGACCGACAGCGUGCGGGCUGCCGGCGCGCCCCCUGCCUGCAAGCACCUAGCCGAGAAGAAGACGAUGACCAACCCCACGACCGUCAUCGAGGUCUACCCGGACACCACCGAGGUGAACGACUAUUACCUGUGGUCCAUCUUCAACUUCGUCUACCUCAACUUCUGCUGCCUGGGCUUCAUCGCCUUGGCCUACUCCCUCAAAGUGCGAGACAAGAAGCUUCUCAAUGACCUGAAUGGAGCCGUGGAGGAUGCAAAGACGGCCCGGCUGUUCAACAUCACCAGUUCUGCCCUGGCAGCCUCCUGCAUCAUCCUCGUCUUCAUCUUCCUGCGGUACCCCCUCACCGACUACUAAGGCCCGCCAGGCACGGCUGCUGGCGGAGACAAGCACUGAGACAUGUUUAUUCUCAUGGUCCCUGAAACGCAGGAUCCCAUGAGGUUGGGGCAGGGCAGGGCUUCUUGUCCUGGGGCCCCCUUGAGCUGUGAACUGGGCAGCAAGGCCAUCAGAAGCUGAGUACAGCAAGGGGGCAGUGAGCUUGGCCCUCAGUCCACCCCCUCCGCCUCCUGGCCUCCACCCUGCCUGUGUCUGGGGCCUGGGGGCUUCUCCCCUCGCUGCUGCACCCUGGCUUCCAGCGUCUGUGUCCCUGCCCUCACGUGCCCCUUCCCAGGCUCCUGGGGCCCCUUGGACCUGACACCUAGCAGGAAGGGCUUAUGCAAAAUUGUCCCAGGUUGGGAGGACUCACUCUGUGCUCCCCGACCCUGCCUCCUCCACGAUGUGACCCCGCUCAGAGCCCUUGUGUCUGUGAACUUUCAAUGAAAUACCCAUGCAGCUCCAGCCCAGCCUUCUACUUUGUGUCCCUGGCAGGGCCUGGAGAAGUCUGGAGGCUUUGCAAUCCUCCCUCAGGAACUGCCUGGCGGUCAGGGCCCCGGGUGCUGUGUCCCAACAGACUGCAGGGGACGGUCUGCUCCAUCACAGCUGUGCCAGACAGUGAAUGGGAAGGGGGGGCAUUUGGUGGAGGUACCCCAAACUCGAGUCACUUAGAGGGUCAGGCAGCCUCCUGGGGGGACGGAAGGGGGUGGGGCACAGCCUCAGCUGCCUGCAUUGGCCAAAUCAGAGCAAAGGAAACCACAAAUUCACUCGGAAGGAAGCAGCAGGCAGAGACGAUAGACGCCUGGCUAACCCCUGUCCCUCCUGGAGGGCUCUGGGACCUGGACAGGCCCCUUUACCUCUCUCGUGCCCAUCUCCUUAGCUGUAAAAUAGGAAAAUGGCCUUUCACUUCUAUAAUCACUGUGAAAAUGAACGGAAGAUGCCUUUCAAAGGCCGAGGCCAGCGCCCUGACGGCCCAUGGCAUGUGCAGUCCACAAUGUGGGAGGCAGGAUGCAGGGAUGGGCUCUGUCCCCUUGGAACUCAGGCACAGUCAUGGGGGUGCCGGUCAGCCCUGAAGACAAGCUGAUGAGGGUGCACUAGGAAAAGUGCAGGGCAUCGGCGAGGCACACGAAGGAGGUGGGGAGGUGAAGAUGGAGAAGAAGCCGAGGCAGUGGCCAUGGGUGUGGAGCUUCGCGCUGUGGGUGCCCAGCUGGUCUGGGAAACCGCAGGAAAUCCCGCAGCUCAGGUGCGCAGUGGGAAGGACUUGCUAUUCCGUGGGAAGGCAGGCAAACCUUCCCAGGGAAGGGGCAUGGCCGUGCGCCUCAUGUUUUGGGAAGCUCGUGCCCUCUGGGGUAGCGAGGCCAGCUUGGAGGGGAGUCCAGUGGACAGAGGUGGAUGCAAGUGGAGGGAGCUGAGCCUGGGCUGGGGCUGGCAGCAGAGGGCUGGACAGCAGGGCGCCUGCGUGGCAGCUGUGCAGUCAGUGGGGUUGACUGGUUUGGAAGGUAAGGUGGGGGAGAAGCCCGGAGGAUUCCUGUCCCUUGACUUGGACAGCCCAGUGGAGAGGGCUGUGUACCAAGGGCAGGAAACCAGGGAGAAGAAGAUGUUGACUUUAAGAUACCAAGCAGAGAAGGGAAGAGCCUUCUGGGCUGGAGACGUGGGGUGCCUCAGAAGGGAGGACCUUGAGCUAGCAGCAGAUGGGACAAACGCAGGGGACAGGGCACAGCCGUGGCAGGAGUGCAGCGAGCAAGAUUCUGGUCACAGUCCUGACCCAGAAACCUGCAGAGGAAGGGAGGGUGGCCAGCACCUGCCCGUGGGCCUGGGGUGCAGCCCAGGCAGAGGUGGAUGGAGGGGGUGCUCAGGGAAGAGGGGAGGGGAGUGUGUGACCUCAAAAUGGGAGGGCUUGGGGGUCAGAGUCGAGAGAGGGGACAGGGUGGGGACCAUGUGGGACUCUUGAGCACUGACCCUUGAACCCAGGCAGUGGUGGGAUGGGAGGGCAGGAGGCGGCGGGCUGCGAGGCUGAUGCGGGGCUGCACGGAGCUGUCAUUGAGCCUCUUGGAGGAUGGUGGGAGAAGUGCCAGGGGCGGCUGAAAGCCUUGCCGAGACUGUGGGCAGCCUGGUUGUGGGCACUUCGGAUGCUUGCACCAUUAGACCCAGAGGCUUCCUGGACAAGCCUGGGCUGGAAGAGGAUGGCAGAGGCUGCUGGGCCUUGGAAGAGAGAGGGUCCUGGCUUCUAGUUCCUGGGGCAGCUAAGGCCAACCCCAGUGUCCAGGUGUCUUCCAUGUUAUGCCUGGGAGGGAAGAAAGUAGAGGGGCAAAUGCUUUCUUUGCCUAUUUUCCUUAAACAUUUGGUGGCAGUGCUGGUGGCUGCCUGGGACAGGGGCCAGGAGGAAACACCCCUGCAUUAGGGAAGCCCUCAGCCAGCUUUUCCCUGGGAUGUUCCUGCGCCUGGCUGAAGCUUUCUGAGUUCAUGUUGGGGAAAUGGAACGGUCACCUUCCAGCCAGUAAAGGCACCCCUAGCUCUUGGGAUGUUUGUAUCCAACUCCGGGCAAUGUGGGGCUACAAAGGCCCCUGGCUUCCAUACCCUGGGGACCGGGGGAGGGCUGGUGCUCCCGCGGUGGGUGUCCACGGUGAGGUCAGGCCCCCACAGCAGGUGCAUUCUCGCCCUCAGCAGGCAGGCAAGCAGGCAUCAGCUCCGGCGCUGGUCUCUGGCUUCGAAGUCUGUGUCUUUGCCUGUCUGUACUCAUGCCUGACCUGCUGGCGCUCCCUGUCCACUGCACUCCUCCCACCUCAUUUUUAUGUGAUUUUGCACAGUGCCUGGCAGACAUUUGACAUUCAAUAAACAUUGUACGAACGAAAGAAUCAA